GGGGCCUCGCCGGCGCCGUCAAGUAGCCUGGGGGACAGGCCGGCGCGGCUGGGAGCGGGUGGGCGGCCGGGAGGCCGGAGCAGCACGGCCGCAGGACCUGGAGCUCCGGCUGCGUCUUCCCGCAGCGCUACCCGCCAUGCGCCUGCCGCGCCGGGCCGCGCUGGGGCUCCUGCCGCUUCUGCUGCUGCUGCCGCCCGCGCCGGAGGCCGCCAAGAAGCCGACGCCCUGCCACCGGUGCCGGGGGCUGGUGGACAAGUUUAACCAGGGGAUGGUGGACACCGCAAAGAAGAACUUUGGCGGCGGGAACACGGCUUGGGAGGAAAAGACGCUGUCCAAGUACGAGUCCAGCGAGAUUCGCCUGCUGGAGAUCCUGGAGGGGCUGUGCGAGAGCAGCGACUUCGAAUGCAAUCAGAUGCUAGAGGCGCAGGAGGAGCACCUGGAGGCCUGGUGGCUGCAGCUGAAGAGCGAAUAUCCUGACUUAUUCGAGUGGUUUUGUGUGAAGACACUGAAAGUGUGCUGCUCUCCAGGAACCUACGGUCCCGACUGUCUCGCAUGCCAGGGCGGAUCCCAGAGGCCCUGCAGCGGGAAUGGCCACUGCAGCGGAGAUGGGAGCAGACAGGGCGACGGGUCCUGCCGGUGCCACAUGGGGUACCAGGGCCCGCUGUGCACUGACUGCAUGGACGGCUACUUCAGCUCGCUCCGGAACGAGACCCACAGCAUCUGCACAGCCUGUGACGAGUCCUGCAAGACGUGCUCGGGCCUGACCAACAGAGACUGCGGCGAGUGUGAAGUGGGCUGGGUGCUGGACGAGGGCGCCUGUGUGGAUGUGGACGAGUGUGCGGCCGAGCCGCCUCCCUGCAGCGCUGCGCAGUUCUGUAAGAACGCCAACGGCUCCUACACGUGCGAAGAGUGUGACUCCAGCUGUGUGGGCUGCACAGGGGAAGGCCCAGGAAACUGUAAAGAGUGUAUCUCUGGCUACGCGAGGGAGCACGGACAGUGUGCAGAUGUGGACGAGUGCUCACUAGCAGAAAAAACCUGUGUGAGGAAAAACGAAAACUGCUACAAUACUCCAGGGAGCUACGUCUGUGUGUGUCCUGACGGCUUCGAAGAAACGGAAGAUGCCUGUGUGCCGCCGGCAGAGGCUGGUGAGUGGCACGGCUGCCCUCCACACAGGCUGCCCUCCCCUGGGCCGCAGGGCUUGCACGUAGACUGGCUGCUUGGUCUGAAAUCCACACAGAUGGUGGCCUUGAGAUGGUGAGAGGGGGAUUCCCGGAAGACAGGUGCAUGACAUCUCUGUGUGGGCACGCUUGCGCGAGAGGUACUGGCUUCCUGAGGAUGAAGCCCCAGGUUCACAGCUCAAACGGAAGUUCAGGCGAUGAAGGGGGAAGUCUCUGAAGCUCAGACCUCAGCGGGCGAUGAGCAGAGGAGCAGACGCAGGAGAAGAGGCAGCUAAAGAGCUGGAAAAGUCAUCCGGGGAAGCUGCCCAGGGUGCCGCAGAGACAGGGACAGGCAGGAAGUGGUGGAGGGCAAGCGGGUCCCCCACACCUGUUUCCUGGGGCUACCUUACCAAGAACCAGGAACUUAGGGCUCCAGCAACAGAAAUGUGCCGCUCACAGGAGCCAGAAGUCAGAGGCCCAGACGCAAGCAGGCUGCUUCCUUGGGAGGCUGGGUGGGCGCGUCUGUUCCGGGCCUCUGUCCUCGCCUGGGGAUGCCACCUGCUCCCCGUGUCUUCACGUGGUCUCCAUGCGGGUGUCUGUCUCUGUCCAAACCUCCCCUCUUUGUAAGGACACCAGUCACUAAUGCCCUCAUGUUAACCUGGCCAGUGGUAAAGACCCUAUUUCCAAACAAGGUCACAAUCACAGGUACUGGGAGUAAAGACUUCAGCGUGUUUUGGGGGACAUAAAUCUGCCCGUGACAGUCCUCACAGAAGUCUAGAAUAUAGAGAGUGGGAAAGAAGCAGUGUUCAAGGAGAUAUUGGCUAAGGGUUUUUCAGAAUGAAUAAGGCACGAUUCAGAUUCCAGAAGCUGUUUCCUGAGCAGGACAAAUAAAAGCAAUUCCACAUCUAGAAGCAUCGUAGUAAACAGCAACAGCAAGACAGAACUGAGGGGUUAGCAGAGACGGACAGGCCAGAAGACAAGGCUGCCUGCUACCCCCUC